GAAAGGUCGGCGGCGCCGGCACUGCAGCUGGGGCUGAGAAGCCAGGACGGCCCGAGAACUGACAGACGGAGUGACAGACGGACUGACCAUGGCCGACCAGCCAAAACCCAUCAGCCCGCUCAAGAACCUGCUGGCCGGCGGCUUUGGCGGCGUGUGCCUGGUGUUCGUCGGUCACCCUCUGGACACGGUCAAGGUCCGACUGCAGACACAGCCACCGAGUUUGCCUGGACAACCUCCCAUGUACUCUGGGACCUUUGACUGUUUCCGGAAGACUCUUUUUAGAGAGGGCAUCACGGGGCUAUAUCGGGGAAUGGCUGCCCCUAUCAUCGGGGUCACUCCCAUGUUUGCCGUGUGCUUCUUUGGGUUUGGUUUGGGGAAGAAACUACAACAGAAACACCCAGAAGAUGUGCUCAGCUAUCCCCAGCUUUUUGCAGCUGGGAUGUUAUCUGGCGUAUUCACCACAGGAAUCAUGACUCCUGGAGAACGGAUCAAGUGCUUAUUACAGAUUCAGGCUUCUUCAGGAGAAAGCAAGUACACUGGUACCUUGGACUGUGCAAAGAAGCUGUACCAGGAGUUUGGGAUCCGAGGCAUCUACAAAGGGACUGUGCUUACCCUUAUGCGAGAUGUCCCAGCUAGUGGAAUGUAUUUCAUGACAUAUGAAUGGCUGAAAAAUAUCUUCACUCCGGAGGGAAAGAGGGUCAGUGAGCUCAGUGCCCCUCGGAUCUUGGUGGCUGGGGGCAUUGCAGGGAUCUUCAACUGGGCUGUGGCAAUCCCCCCAGAUGUGCUCAAGUCUCGAUUCCAGACUGCACCUCCUGGGAAAUAUCCUAAUGGUUUCAGAGAUGUGCUGAGGGAGCUGAUCCGGGAUGAAGGAGUCACAUCCUUGUACAAAGGGUUCAAUGCAGUGAUGAUCCGAGCCUUCCCAGCCAAUGCGGCCUGUUUCCUUGGCUUUGAAGUUGCCAUGAAGUUCCUUAAUUGGGCCACCCCCAACUUGUGAGGCUGAAGGCUGCUCAAGUUCACUUCUGGAUGCUGGAAGCUGUCGUUGAGGAGAAGGAGUAGUAAGCAGAACUAAGCAGUCUUGGAGGGCAAGGGGAGGGGAAUGGUGAGAUCCGAGCCCUGUGCAUGGACUUGGUGAGACUGUUGCCUUAAUGACAUCCUGCACCGUGUAUAACUUAGUGUGUCAUUUUGAAACUUGAAUUCAUUCUUAUCAAUUUAAGGGAUCUUAAAAGGAUUUGGAAAUGGAACAAGUAGCUUCCAGACCAGAUACUACCUGUGGCAAGAAUGCUGCCUACCAGUUAACUGCUGGUCCUACCACAGUCAAAGUAUUCCUCAUUAAAGAGAGAAUCUCAGGUUCUCACUGGAGGCACUGUGCAUAUUUUCAACCAGAUCACCAGGAGCUGAGAUCUUCUUCAGUCCCUAGCCAGGAAUACCCAUUUGAUUUCCAGGGUGCCAUCUAAUCCUGGGCUGUACAUGUGGAUAUGGACUUGAGGCCCACCUCUGUGUCCAAGUGGAUUGAGCAUAUAUGCCUAGGAGGAGAUAGACUGUUAAUCGUUGGAUUUUGAUUUUUUUUUUUUAUGCCUGCAAAUAAUCAAAAGUAAAACUGGAGUAGCCUAAUUUUCUGGGAGCAGGUGGAGAACUUUCCCUCCUACACAGUGAGGACAGUCCCAGUCUGCUGGGAUAAGUGAGAAAGCCCAGGGUGUAGGAAGGCCCUUUUUACAUACUCUUUUCUCAUGAGAGCUCACUAUUUUAACAAUAAACAAUAAACGUUGUUUCUAAUUUUU